GCCGUUGUUUCUGGUUCCAGCUGGAGCUCCGGAUCUCGUUUUUACUGCUCUGUGUCCUUAGCCUCUGUGGCCCUGUGACCUGUAGGUAUUUGGAGAUCCACAGCUAGGACGCCAGGACCCCCUGGAAGCUUAGAAAUGGGAUCGUUGACAUUUUGGGAUGUGACCAUAGAAUUCGCUCUGGAGGAGUGGCAAUGCCUGGACAUGGCUCAGCAGAAUUUAUAUAGGAAUGUUAUGUUAGAGAACUACAGAAACCUGGUCUUCCUGGGUAUCGCUGUCUCUAAGCUAGACUUGAUAACUUGUCUGAAGCAAGGGAAAGAGCCUUGGAAUAUGAAGAGACAUGAGAUGGUAACUAAACCCCCAGUUAUUAGUUCUCAUUUUACACAAGACUUUUGGCCAGAUCAGAGCAUAAAAGAUUCUUUCCAAGAAAUAAUAUUGAGAACAUAUGCAAGAUGUGGACAUAAGAAUUUACGAUUAAGAAAAGAUUGUGAAAGUGUCAAUGAGGGUAAGAUGCACGAAGAAGCUUAUAAUAAACUUAACCAAUGUUGGACAACUACCCAGGGAAAAAUAUUUCAGUGUAACAAAUAUGUGAAAGUCUUUCAUAAAUAUUCAAAUUCAAAUAGAUAUAAGAUUAGACACACUAAAAAGAAAACUUUCAAAUGUAUGAAAUGUAGCAAAUCAUUUUUCAUGCUUUCACACUUAAUUCAACAUAAGAGAAUUCAUACUAGAGAGAAUAUCUACAAAUGUGAAGAACGUGGCAAAGCCUUUAAAUGGUUCUCAACCCUUAUUAAACAUAAGAUAAUUCAUACUGAAGACAAACCCUACAAAUAUAAGAAAUGUGGCAAAGCUUUUAACAUCUCUUCAAUGUUCACUAAAUGUAAGAUAAUUCAUACUGGAAAGAAACCCUGCAAAUGUGAAGAAUGUGGCAAAGUUUUUAACAAUUCCUCAACCCUUAUGAAACAUAAGAUAAUUCAUACUGGGAAGAAACCAUAUAAAUGUGAAGAAUGUGGCAAAGCUUUUAAGCAAUCCUCACACCUUACUAGACAUAAAGCAAUUCAUACUGGAGAGAAACCCUACAAAUGCGAAGAAUGUGGCAAAGCUUUUAACCAUUUCUCAGCCCUUAGAAAACAUCAGAUAAUUCAUACUGGAAAGAAACCCUACAAAUGUGAAGAAUGUGGCAAAGCUUUUAGCCAGUCCUCAACCCUUAGAAAACAUGAGAUAAUUCAUACUGAAGAGAAACCCUACAAAUAUGAAGAAUGCGGCAAAGCUUUUAGCAAUUUGUCAGCCCUUAGAAAACAUGAGAUAAUUCAUACUGGACAGAAACCCUACAAAUGUGAAGAAUGUGGUAAAGCUUUUAAGUGGUCCUCAAAACUUACUGUACAUAAGGUAAUUCAUACUGCAGAGAAACCCUGCAAAUGUGAAGAAUGUGGCAAAGCUUUUAAGCGUUUCUCAGCCCUUAGAAAACAUAAGAUAAUUCAUACUGGAAAGCAACCCUACAAAUGUGAAGAAUGCAGCAAAGCUUUUAGCAAUUUUUCAGCCCUUAGAAAACAUGAGAUAAUUCAUACUGGAGAGAAACCCUACAAAUGUGAAGAAUGUGGUAAAGCUUUUAAGUGGUCCUCAAAACUUACUGUACAUAAGGUAAUUCAUAUGGAAGAGAAACCUUGCAAAUGUGAAGAAUGUGGCAAAGCUUUUAAGCAUUUCUCAGCCCUUAGAAAACAUAAGAUAAUUCAUACUGGAAAGAAACCCUACAAAUGUGAAGAAUGUGGCAAAGCUUUUAACAAUUCCUCAACCCUUAUGAAACAUAAGAUAAUUCAUACUGGGAAGAAACCAUACAAAUGUGAAGAAUGUGGCAAAGCUUUUAAGCAAUCUUCACAUCUUACUAGACAUAAAGCAAUUCAUACUGGGGAGAAACCCUACAAAUGUGAAGAAUGUGGCAAAGCUUUUAACCACUUCUCAGCCCUUAGAAAACAUCAGAUAAUUCAUACUGGAAAGAAACCCUACAAAUGUGAAGAAUGUGGCAAAGCUUUUAGCCAGUCCUCAACCCUUAGAAAACAUGAGAUAAUUCAUACUGGAGAGAAACCCUACAAAUGUGAAGAAUGUGGUAAAGCUUUUAAGUGGUCCUCACACCUUACUAGACAUAAAGUAAUUCAUACUGAAGAGAAACCCUACAAAUGUGAAGAAUGUGGCAAGGCUUUUAACCAUUUCUCAGCCCUUAGGAAACAUAAGAUAAUUCAUACUGGAAAGAAACCCUACAAAUGUGAAGAAUGUGGCAAAGCUUUUAGCCAGUCCUCAACUCUUAGAAAACAUGAGAUAAUUCAUACUGGAGAGAAACCCUACAAAUGUGAAGAAUGUGGUAAAGCUUUUAAGUGGUCCUCAAAACUUACUGUACAUAAGGUAAUUCAUACUGCAGAGAAACCCUGCAAAUGUGAAGAAUGUGGCAAAGCUUUUAAGCAUUUCUCAGCCCUUAGAAAACAUAAGAUAAUUCAUACUGGAAAGAAACCCUAUAAAUGUGAAGAAUGUGGCAAAGCUUUUAACAAUUCCUCAACCCUUAGAAAACAUGAGAUAAUUCAUACUGGAGAGAAAUCCUACAAAUGUGAAGAAUGUGGUAAAGCUUUUCAGUGGUCCUCAAAACUUACUUUACAUAAGGUAAUUCAUAUGGAGAGAAACCCUGCAAAUGUGAAGAAUGUGGCAAAGCUUUUAAACAUUUCUCAGCCCUUAGAAAACAUGAGAUAAUUCAUACUGGAAAGAAACCCUACAAAUGUGAAGAAUGUGGCAAAGCUUUUAACAAUUCCUCAACCCUUAGGAAACAUAAGAUAAUUUAUACUGGGAAGAAACCAUACAAAUGUGAAGAAUGUGGCAAAGCUUUUAAGCAGUCCUCACACCUUACUAGACAUAAAGCAGUUCAUACUGGGGAGAAGCCCUACAAAUGUGGAGAAUGUGGAAAAGCUUUUAACAAUUCCUCAACCCUUAAGAAACAUAAGCUAAUUCAUACUAGGGAGAAAUCGUACAAAUGUGAAGAAUGUGGCAAAGCUUUUAGCAAUUUCUCAGCCCUUAGGAAACAUAAGAUAAUUCAUACUGGGGAGAAACCAUACAAAUGUGAAGAAUGUGGUAAAGCUUUUAAGUGGUCUCAAAACUUAUGGAACAUAAGGUAAUUCAUACUGUAGAGAAACCCUACAAAUGUGAAGAAUGUGGCAAAGCUUUUAAGCAUUUCUCAGCCCUUAGAAAACAUGAGAUAAUUAUACUGGAAAGAAACCCUACAAAUGUGAAGAAUGUGGCAAAGCUUUUAACAAUUCCUCAACCCUUAUGAAACAUAAGAUAAUUCAUACUGGGGAGAAACCGUACAAAUGUGAAGAAUGUGGCAAAGGUUUUAACAAUUUCUCGACCCUUAUGAAACAUAAGAUAAUUCAUACUGGGGAGAAACCGUACAAAUGUGAAGAAUGUGGCAAAGCUUUUAAGCAAUCCUCACACCUUACUAAACAUAAAUCAAUUCAUACUGGAGAGAAACCCUACAAAUGUGAAGAACGUGGCAAAGCUUUUAGCCAUUUCUCACGCCUUACUAAACAUAGGAUAAUUCAUACUGGAAAGAAACCCUACAAAUGUGAAGAGUGUGGUAAAGCAUUUAGUCCUCAAACCUUACUAAACAUAAGAUAAUUCAUUCUGGAGAGAAACCCUACAAAUGUGAAGAAUGUGGCAAAGCCUUUAACCAGUCCUCACACCUUACUCAACAUAAAACAAUUCAUACUGGAGGGAAAACCUACAAAUGUGAAGAAUGUGGCAAAGCUUUUAACCAUCUUUCAGCCCUUACUAAACAUAAGAUAAUUCAUACUGGGGAGAAGCCCUAAAAAUGUGAAGAAUGUGUCAAAGCUUUCAACCAUUUUACAAACCUUAAUACACAUAAGAUAAUUUAUACUAGAGACAGACCCUCCAUAUGUGAAGAAUGUGGCAAAGCUUUUAACCAGUCCUCAAGCCUUAAUAGGCAGAAAACAAUUCAUGCUGGAGAGAAACCCCACAAAUGUAAAGAAUGUGGCAAAGCCUUUAACCAGUCCUCACACCUUAAAUACACAUAAAAUAAUUGAUACUGGAGGAAAACCCUACAAAUAUAAUAAAGGUGACAAAGCUUUUAACCAUUGCUCAGCUGUUACUCAAAAUGAGAGAAUUCCUAAAGAAGAUAAACUCCACAAAUGUGAAUAAUAUGGCAAAGCUUUUAACUGGUCCUCAAAUCUUACUGAAUGUAAGAUAAUUCAUACUGAAGAUAAACCCUUCAAAUGUGAGGAAUGUGGCAAAGCUUUUAAUCAGUCCUCAAAUCUUACUGAACAUAAGAUAAUUCAUAGUAGAGACAAACACUGCAAAUAUGAAGAAUGGGCAAAGCUUUUAACCAGUCCUCAAACUUUACUCAACAUAAAAUAAUUUAUCUUGGAGAGGAACACUACAAAUUUAAAGAAUUUGGCAAAACUUUUAACUGCUUCUCAAAACUUACUGAACAUAAGAUAAUUCAUACUGGAGAGAUACUUUACAAAUGUGAAGAAUGUGGCAAAGCUUCUAACGGGUUCUCAGAUCUUACUGAAUAUAAGAUAAAUUAGAGAGAAACCCGCCUCAUGUGAAGAGUGUGGCAAAACUUUUAACUGGUCCUCAAACCUUACUGAACAUAAGAUAAUUCAUACUGAAGAGAAACCCUACAAAUAUGAAAACUGUGGCAAAGCUUUUAACUGGUUUUCAGACCUUACUCAACAGAAAAUAGUUGAUACUGAAGACAAACUCUAGAAAUGUGAAGAAUGUGGCAAUGCUUUUAAUCAGUUAAACUUUAUUAGACAUAAGAAAAUUCGUACUGGAGAAAAACCCUACAAAUGUGAAGAAAGUGGCAAUGCUUUUAGCCAGUCCUCAACUCUUGCUAAACAACAUAAUUCAAUGGGAGAGAAACCCUACAAAUGUGAAUAAUGCCAUAAGCAUUCUUCAAUUUUUUUUUUUUUUUUUUUGAAACAGAGUUUCGCCCUAGUUGCCCAGGCUCUGGAGUGCAGUGGCACAAUCUCGGCUCACUGCAACCUCCGCCUCCUGGGUUUUCAAGCGAUUCUCCUGCCUCAGCCUCCCGAGUAGCAGGGACUAUAGGCAUGUGCCACCACGCCCACCUAAUUUUGUAUUUUUAGUAGAGACGGGGUUUCUCCAUGUUGGUCAAGCUGGUCUCGAACUCCCGACCUCUGGUGAUCUGCCCGCCUCGGCCUCCCAAAGUGCUGGGAUUAAAGGCGUGAGCCACCGUGCCCAGCCUAAUUCUUCAAUUCUUAAUAAACAAUUUAUACUGAAGAGAAACCCUACAAACGUGAAGAAUGUUGCAAAGCUUUUAACGUCCUCAAACCUUACUGAACAUAAGAUAAUUCAUAAUGGAAACUAGCCCUACAAAUAUGAAGAAUGUGGCAAACACUGUAACCAUUUCUCACAUCUUACCACACAUUAAGAUAAUUCAUACUGAAGAGAAACCCGACAAAUGUGAAGAAUGUAACAAAGUCUUUAACUGGUCUUCAACUCAUACUAAAUAUAAGAGAAUUCAUACAGAAGAUAAAUUUUAUAAAUAUGAAGAAUGUGACAAAAGCUUUAAAAACAUUUCAACCCUUAUUACACAUAAGAUAAUUUAUGUUGUAGAGAAAUUCUACAAAUGUGAAGAAUGUGGCAAAGUUUUUUUUUUUUUUUUGAAAUGGAGUCUCACUCUGUCGCCCAAAUUGGAGUGCAAUGGUGCAAUCUCAGUUCAUUGCAACCUCCGCCUCCUGGGUUCAAGCGAUUCUCUGGCCUCAACCUCCCAAGCAGCUGGGAUUGCAGGCGCCUGCCACCACGCCCAGCUAAUUUUUGUAUUUUUAGUAGAGACGGGGUUUCACCAUUUUGACCAGGCUGGUUUUGAACUCCUGACCUCAAGUGAUCCACCCGCCUUGGCCUCCCAAAGUGCCCCAAAGUGCUGGGAUUACAAGCAUGAGCCAUUGAGCCCGGUCGAAUGUGGCAAAGUUUUUAAUAAGUUAUCAAAUCAUACUGGAGAGAAGCUCUACAAACCUAAAAGACAUGACAGUGCUCUUGAGAACACCUUAAACUUUUCUAAACAUAAAAGAAAUCAUAGUGUCAAGAAGCCCUAGAUGUGAGUCAUGUCACAAAGCCUUUAAAUGGUUGUCACACUUGAGUAUAAGCUAAUUUAUCCUAGAGAAAACUAUGAAGAAUGUGGCAAAAUAUUUAACCAAUACUCACACCUUAUCGCAUAGGAAAGCAUUUAUACUUGAAAAAAAAUGUACACCUAUGAAGAAUGUGGAAAAGCCAUUAAUAUCUGCUCACAUCUUAACAUCACAGAGUUUAUACUUAAAACAAAUAUUAAAAAUGCAAUUACUGUGAGAAUAUCUUUUAGAAAAUAUAAACCUUAGAAUGGUGAAGAGUAUUUCUUUUGAUGACAAACAUUACAAAUAUAAAGACGGUUGUAGUACUAUAUUUGUAUCACAGAUCUUAUUGUGCAUAUUUUGUGCUAGAGAAAAACCCUAAAGUUGCUCAAACUUUGUUCAAUAUCAGGGAAUGUAUAAUAGAGAAAAAAACCUGCAAAUGUAAUAAAUUUGGAAAAAAGUUUAUAAACUACAGCUUAGAAAACAGAGUAAGUUUUUUUUGUAGAUGCAGUAAAUAUGAAAAAUAUUCAAUCCAAAAUUAACUCUGUAAAUGUCAGAGAAUUCACAGUAGAAAUGAUAAGGCACUGGCACUUCAGACUACACUAAAUCAGAGUGUUGAGUAAAAAAAAUAAUUUCAAUCUAAAAUUUAGAUAAGUUAUUUGCAUAUAACUUAAAAAAGAGGAGGUGAUUUUUUGGAGAAUUAUAAUUACAUUUGAAGUAUACUUUUUGUAUACUUCAAAUAUCAAAAAAAUUAACAUCACAAUAUUGAAAAAAAUUACAGACUCUGAAAAGCAAAUAAGGAUGUAAUUCAACUCUCAAGUUACUUCAUGCUCUUCAUUCCUACUUUAUUUACAUGUGAAAGCAUGCGAUCAAUUGUUGCUGCAUCAGAGAUAUGAAAGAUUCUUUUUUAUUAGAUGGGCAUUAUUUAUGACCUUUUUCAUAAAAGAGAAAGGAUAUUAAAAUAUAAAAUGCAUGAUAAAAAUCUAAAUGGAGAGGCUUUUUGUGGUUAACUUAAAAUAUUGAGUGAUGUAUGAGGUAGGUGUUCUGAGGAAUAUAUUUUUGUGCAUUAUAGUGAGAAAAACAUUUUAAAAUUUUAGUUAAAAUUAAAAUUAAAUUAGUGAUGUAUUAUAUUAGUUGUGCUUUUAUGUAAUGUAGUACAUUCAUAAAUUUUUAGAUUAUAUGUAAACUUAAUUUUUUAAACAUUUUUUGACAUGUUAAGUCUGUUGUACAUUCAAUGAAGUGUUAUUAUGCCACUCGCUUUAACCUAUCCCACCUUACUCAAGGGUGUAGGUAAGAGAUGGCAACAGUUUACUAUUUGGUAAGAGUGGAAUAACAUCUCUAGUAAUCUCUUUUUUUCAGUGGCUUUAACCUGCAAAUAAAUUAAAGAAUAUUGUUCUCGUAGGUUACAUUUUUAUACUUUUAAUCUUAUUUAAACUUCUUUUUUUUUUUGCCUUGACAAAUUUAAACUUAUUUUUCUUAACUUUUAUGGGUACAUAGUGUGUAGAUAUAUUUCUGCCAUAUAUAGCAUAUUUUGAUACCAGCAUAAAAUAUGUAAUAAUCACGUCAGGGUAAAUGAGGGAUUCUUCACCUUCAACAUUUAUUCCUUGAAUUACAAGCAAUCCAAAUCUACACUUUUAGUCACUUUGAAAUAUAAAACUAAAUUGUUAUCUUUAUUAUAGCGUCAUUUUUGUGGUCAUAAUAAAAAUCAUAUAGGAAUGUAAAUAAAAUCUAUACAUAUCUGG